CUUCCUCCCGCGGGCGGCCCAGCCCUAGCGCCCCGCGCUCCGCGGGCAGCCCCCUGCCGCCGCGCCAUGUCCGCCGGCUGGUUCCGGCGCCGCUUCCUGCCUGGGGAGCCGCUCCCCGCGCCGCGGCCGCCUGGGCCGCAUGCCAGCCCCGUGCCCUACCGACGGCCCCGCUUCCUUCGCGGCUCCAGCUCCAGCCCCGGGGCGGCCGACGCCUCGCGCCGCCCAGACUCCCGGCCCGUGCGCAGCCCCGCACGAGGACGCACGCUACCCUGGAAUGCAGGCUACGCCGAGAUUAUCAAUGCAGAGAAAUCUGAAUUCAAUGAGGAUCAAGCCGCCUGUGGGAAGCUGUGCAUCCGGAGAUGUGAGUUUGGGGCUGAAGAAGAGUGGCUGACCCUGUGCCCAGAGGAGUUCCUGACAGGCCAUUACUGGGCACUGUUCGAUGGGCACGGCGGUCCUGCAGCAGCCAUCUUGGCUGCCAACACCCUGCACUCCUGCUUGCGCCGGCAGCUGGAGGCCGUGGUGGAAGGCUUGGUGGCCACUCAGCCCCCCAUGCACCUCAAUGGCCGCUGCAUCUGCCCCAGUGACCCUCAGUUUGUGGAGGAAAAGGGCAUCAGGGCAGAAGACUUGGUGAUCGGGGCAUUGGAGAGUGCCUUUCAGGAAUGUGAUGAGGUGAUCGGGCGGGAGCUGGAGGCCUCAGGCCAGAUGGGCGGCUGCACAGCCCUGGUGGCUGUGUCCCUGCAGGGAAAGCUGUACAUGGCCAAUGCUGGGGAUAGCAGGGCCAUCUUGGUGCGGAGAGAUGAGAUACGGCCACUGAGCUUCGAGUUCACCCCAGAGACUGAGCGGCAGCGGAUCCAGCAGCUGGCCUUUGUCUAUCCUGAGCUUCUGGCUGGUGAGUUCACCCGACUGGAGUUCCCUCGGCGGCUGAAGGGGGAUGACUUGGGACAGAAGGUUUUGUUCAGGGAUCACCACAUGAGUGGCUGGAGCUACAAACGUGUGGAGAAAUCGGAUCUCAAGUACCCACUGAUCCAUGGACAGGGUAGGCAGGCUCGGUUACUAGGAACACUGGCUGUCUCCCGGGGCCUGGGAGACCAUCAGCUCAGAGUCCUGGACACAAACAUCCAGCUCAAGCCCUUCUUGCUCUCUGUGCCACAGGUGACUGUGCUGGAUGUGGACCAGCUGGAGCUACAGGAGGAUGAUGUGGUUGUCAUGGCAACUGAUGGACUCUGGGAUGUACUGUCCAACGAGCAGGUGGCAUGGCUGGUGCGGAGCUUCCUCCCUGGGAACCAAGAGGACCCACACAGUCUAUCUGCAGGAUGGUCUUCACAGGUUCUCAAAGCUGGCCCAGAUGCUGAUACACAGCACACAGGGAAAGGAAGACAGUCUCACAGAGGAAGGGCAGGUGUCCUACGAUGACGUCUCUGUGUUCGUGAUUCCCUUGCACAGUCAGGGCCAAGAGAGCAGUGACCACUGAGGAUUCAGACACUGUAUCCCAGAACUGCUCUAGUGCCCGGGUGUGGUCUGGGCAUCCCUCCAGUGUGACCAAGAGCAAAUCCUGCCUGCCCUAUCCCUAGCCACCGCCCAGUGCUCUCACUAUCCACCUCAACACACAUCCAUCUCAAGAGGAACAUUUAUACCAGGCAGUCAGAGCUGGAAGUGUAUGGAGAGCCCAGCCCACCAGGUCCUGCCUUUUGCGGUGAUAACCUUCUCUGGCAGAGUGACUUUACAACUUAACUAGGAAACCCAUGUGAGGCUCCUCAGACAGGAUCUUGAACAGCCCAAAGUAUCAUUCUCAGAUAGGGGCACCCAAGCUAAGGGUAUUAGCCAAAGAUGCCAGGAUGGGUAGCUAGCCCAUGUUUAGAUCCAGGUCUCCAAUUCAUGGUUAUCAGGGCAUGUGUUCAACAACCCCCAAAGUCCACGCAGGUGGCUUGUAGAAACCUUUGGGCAGCCUCAUGUCUGCUAAAACAGCCAUCUUCAAGACAGCCCCUGAAAAGAGACCAGUUCAGGUCCUGCCCUGCUGUUCUUUGCUGGAGAUGAGGAACAGGUGCUGGGGCUAAAGUUUGGGGUAGAGCACAAGGGACAAGAGGAACUCUUGGAGUUGGCUGGGUGAGAGGGCUCUCCAUUUGCUACCUGUAGUAGCCUGCCUCUUAACUGGUUGCUUCUCCCUAGUUCCAGCCCUGCCCUGGUCUGAUGCCCCAACACUGCCCUUGCUUUGUUUUCCCUGUCACCUCCCUAUUAUUAAAUGUUUUCUACAGAAGA